AUGAAACAACUUUUACAGUUCUUGCCAAGUCACGGGCCGCCGCCGCCUCCCCGGAUCCGCCCGCCCGGCUCAGGGGGAGGGACGCCUGGGCCCGGCCGCCCCGCUGCUCCGGCCGCGCGUCCCGCGUCGGUCCGACGGUCUGUCCGUCCUCCUGCCACCCCCCGCCCCCACGGGGCUUCUUUGUGCGGCGCUCCUCGCCGGCCGGUCCCACCUCCAGGCCUCGCCCCUCGCCGUCGCCACCGCCGGACUCUGCCCAGGGGAAUGGUCUGCGAGCCGGGUUUUUGGAGACAGGAAGUGAGGCGUGCGAGCCCCAUGAGCGCGCCGCGGCCCGGGCUGGCGUGCGGGUGCGGCUGCGGCGGCCGCGCGGCGGGGCCCCGGGAGGCGGGUCGCUGAGCGGGGCGCGCGGCCCCGAGGAUGCGGGAGCGGGAGCGG